AGUGUGAAAUCUUCAGAGAAGAAUUUCUCUUUAGUUCUUUGCAAGAAGGUAGAGAUAAAGGUAAGUCUUGGUUUUCCUUUUAGUUAGUUUUGGUUGUUUUGAAAACUUUUCUCAUCACUAUGUUAAAUGUUACUGCUUCUACAGGAUUUAUGGUUAGUUGCAUUUAACAUGAUAAGUCAUUCAUAAAUCUUUCUGUAGAAUUACAUUGGAUAUUUAUAUUUUAGGAAUCACAAAUUACAAUAUUUUUGUUCUACUUAGUUAACAAAUACAAGUAAAAAUAAGAUAAGUUUGCUUAAUACUGGCUCAUUGUACUCUUGGUAAGUUACCAUGAGAAAGAAGGGAAGAAUGUGCUUUCCCUCUGGUAGCCUUAAAAGAAUGUGUUUUUCCUUUCCUUCCCCUUGAAAUAUUUCUUCCCAAGAGCUGUGUGUUUUACAGAGAAAUCGUGAUGGGGGCUGCUUUUUGGGGGCAAGAACAAAAGUGAUAGGAGUGGGCUGCAGGGAACUGUUUCAAAAUAGUAGGACUUUCAUAAUUUAUUUUCUUCUUUUGUAAGGAAAACAAGAUAGAUUCAGACCUCAAAGUGCUAAUCAUGCUCUUUGUAAUAAACAUUUAAAAAUAUAUGUUAUAUUUGCUUAUGCUAUUUAAAAUAAGAAGGUCCGCUUAUUACUUUUUUCAUUUAAAGAGGGUGUGGCCACAUUCCUUUUCUUGUAGGCUCUGUGUCAUAUACAGUCUUUUCAAGUGCUGGCUGGAAAACCUAAAAAGAAGGGAAAUACUUUCUGGGUAGUGUCAGAUACAUUAUCCUAGGGGAAUGUCAGUGAGGCCCUCCAACAGCUAUUCCACUUGAUUGUUGCAUGAGCUAAUGGCCAUAAAACUCCUUAGAAAAGCACAAAGCAAAACUAAAGAAGAGUAUUUACUAGUGUUGGAUAUAUUUGUAAAAGUGAGAUUACAAAUCAUGUAUCUGGCUAUUUUUUUCUUAAACAUGUUCCUUCAAGAAUUUUUCUGUUCGUUCAUUUUAAAUAUUUAUUAAAUGUUCUGAUUUCUUAUGUUCACUGCUAGCUAAUUAACAAGGAUGGAAUUUUUCUUGCCUUGGUUAUAUCUAAAAGAUUGUAAAAACUUUGAGAAAGCAAUGUUGCCCUCUUUCCACAGGAGUAUUUUGGUAGCUGUAAGAGAAUGCACAUUGCAAAUGACUCAAAUGUGGUAAAAUGUUGGUUUCAUAAUUCUGAAAUGGCCUCUUCCCCAAAAGUGACAGUAACACCCUAGCUCCAGGCUCAACCACAUCCAGCACAUAGCCAACAUUUAACAGAUGUUGACAAAAUAGUUAAUAAUAAUAUUAUUAAGGAACCAGCCAGAGUUUCAUGCUUAUUAAAUACUUUUUCAACCAGAAGGUCUGCAAAGGUUGAUUUCUGAAUAUGACGUUAGCUCUCUCUAGACCUAUUAAUUUACGACAUUUCAAAUCAGAGGUAAACCAGCAGACCUAUUAUUUUUCAAUGAUAAACUAUAAACAGUUUUUUGAAGUCAACUAUUUCCUUUUCCUUUAAAAUUGGACAGAAUUUCAUCAGGAAGCUCAGAACAAUCCAAUUUAUAUAAUGCCUUCCUUCAUUAUGCUAAUUUUCUUCAUCUUCAUCUACUUGAAGUAAUAUUUAAGAUUGGCACUUCAGAGCUGUAAAUGGAUCUUAGAUGAUAAUUACUUCAACAUUCUUAUUUUAUAAACGAAGACCCUCUGGAGAAGCUAAAUGUUUUUCUUGAGGUCAGAUCGCCAGAUAAUCAAGAACCAGUAUACUUCAAUUUGUAUUUUAUAUCCUAUAGUUGUGGGUAGAAAAUGUUCAUUAAAUUAGUGUAGAUAUGUUUUUUAAAAUAUUAGCAAUGAUACAUGAUAUUCAUUCAAUAAUACUUAUUAACAUCCUAAAUUCCAGGCAUUUUGCUAGGGAUUGGAAGUACAUACAUAAUGAAUAUUAUUAUUUGUAUGUUAGCACGGGCCUCAUGGCCUGCUCCUGGGGAAUAUAAACAAGCCAAUGGAAAGUGAUAAUACAGAAAGGUGGGGCUGGUGUAGGGGUGAAGUCAGGAUGCUUUGGGAGAGCAUGGAAGGUCACCGAAUCCAGUGCUGAGGAACUAAUGAAGGGUUUCUGAAGAACGUGAUGAGAUCAAUGCUGAUGAGUCACUUAGAAGUAGCAAUUAGUUAGGCAAAGGGAAGUGAAUGUGGAGGAGGAACAAGCAUUCCAGGCAAGAAGAACACCCUAUCGAAAAGCCUGGAAGCAAAACAUUAGUGAGGCUACCUUUCAUAAAUUGCUUUCUGUAAGUCAUGCCAUUGUGUAGUCUUAAUUGCUUUCUCUCACCAGGGAAGGUGUGGGAAGGACUUGUGAAAUACAUAUUCGAGGAAAAACUAUGCACAAGGCCGUGCAUUUAAAAAUAAACUCCCUAAGGCUGGGGUGAAACCUGCUACGGUCUGCGCAAGUUGACUGUUAAUGAAUUUGAUUCUCAGGUACACUUUUUCAAAAAUGGCAAUGGUAUCAGAAUUCCUCAAGCAGGCCUGGUUUAUUGAAAAUGAAGAGCAGGAAUAUGUUCAAACUGUGAAGUCAUCCAAAGGUGGUCCCGGAUCAGCGGUGAGCCCCUAUCCUACCUUCAAUCCAUCCUCGGAUGUCGCUGCCUUGCAUAAGGCCAUAAUGGUUAAAGGUGUGGAUGAAGCAACCAUCAUUGACAUUCUAACUAAGCGAAACAAUGCACAGCGUCAACAGAUCAAAGCAGCAUAUCUCCAGGAAACAGGAAAGCCCCUGGAUGAAACACUGAAGAAAGCCCUUACAGGUCACCUUGAGGAGGUUGUUUUAGCUCUGCUAAAAACUCCAGCGCAAUUUGAUGCUGAUGAACUUCGUGCUGCCAUGAAGGGCCUUGGAACUGAUGAAGAUACUCUAAUUGAGAUUUUGGCAUCAAGAACUAACAAAGAAAUCAGAGACAUUAACAGGGUCUACAGAGAGGAACUGAAGAGAGAUCUGGCCAAAGACAUAACCUCAGACACAUCUGGAGAUUUUCGGAACGCUUUGCUUUCUCUUGCUAAGGGUGACCGAUCUGAGGACUUUGGUGUGAAUGAAGACUUGGCUGAUUCAGAUGCCAGGGCCUUGUAUGAAGCAGGAGAAAGGAGAAAGGGGACAGACGUAAACGUGUUCAAUACCAUCCUUACCACCAGAAGCUAUCCACAACUUCGCAGAGUGUUUCAGAAAUACACCAAGUACAGUAAGCAUGACAUGAACAAAGUUCUGGACCUGGAGUUGAAAGGUGACAUUGAGAAAUGCCUCACAGCUAUCGUGAAGUGCGCCACAAGCAAACCAGCUUUCUUUGCAGAGAAGCUUCAUCAAGCCAUGAAAGGUGUUGGAACUCGCCAUAAGGCAUUGAUCAGGAUUAUGGUUUCCCGUUCUGAAAUUGACAUGAAUGAUAUCAAAGCAUUCUAUCAGAAGAUGUAUGGUAUCUCCCUUUGCCAAGCCAUCCUGGAUGAAACCAAAGGAGAUUAUGAGAAAAUCCUGGUGGCUCUUUGUGGAGGAAACUAAACAUUCCCUUGAUGGUCUCAAGCUAUGAUCAGAAGACUUUAAUUAUAUAUUUUCAUCCUAUAAGCUUAAAUAGGAAAGUUUCUUCAACAGGAUUACAGUGUAGCUACCUACAUGCUGAAAAAUAUAGCCUUUAAAUCAUUUUUAUAUUAUAACUCUGUAUAAUAGAGAUAAGUCCAUUUUUUAAAAAUGUUUUCCCCAAACCAUAAAACCCUAUACAAGUUGUUCUAGUAACAAUACAUGAGAAAGAUGUCUAUGUAGCUGAAAAUAAAAUGACGUCACAAGACAA